AGUCUUCAGAAUCAAUUGGGUGUUUACAUUCAGAAUUAUUUAAAGAUAGAUUUCUCUGUGUGCAUAUUAUCUCACUACCUGUACUGAUAGGAAGUGUCAGACACCCCAGUAUGGCUUCUACUUGUGAACACAGUUUUAGGACAAAAAAAAAAAAUCUUUGCAAUGGAAAGCUCGGUAGGAAGGAGACAGGAGGAAUUAAGGACAGUCUCUAUCAAUGAUGUCAAAGAAGUAGUGAUUGUCUUACCACCCACUCUCAUAAAUGUAGUACGUUGCUUUUGGAAAGCAGUUUUUACAGAAUGCUAUAGUGAGAACCAGGGACCUGACAAACAAGUCCACAAACUUCAGUGGUACCACAGACUGACUCUCUUUUCCUAAUUUUCUUUUAGUUAUCACAUUAUUGCUAAAUAGGCAACUUCUGGCAGGCUGAUUUCAUCUAUAAGUUCAGAUAGGGAAUGUGUGCUCUGCUCUGGGAUGUGUACACUGCUGGGCUGGGCUCUGCCCUGCAGGAGCUUUCACGGUGUGUCCGGCAGCACACCCAUCAGGUGCCGUAACUCCCAAUUGUCCUGAACUACACCAAAGGAUUUUAAUCACCUCAUGACAAUUUUAGGUAGAAAACUGUGCUAAUUUCACUAGAAAAGACUUUGAAAAUUAUUCUUUAAUCUGUAUUGUGGCAUGCAUGGUCAAUAUCCAAUAAUUUUUCUUGAAGAGUCUGUGAGCCCACCAUCAGACCUUACUUGGAAAUGGCGGUAUUGUAUUUCGGUUUCUCCGGGCACUUAACGUCAGGAAAUUAAGUUCAGCUCCAUUAUUUUGUUGCAUCUUUGAAUAGUCUGUGGAGCGUUGAUAUCCUAAUGCUCCUUAUUUAAAAGUGGGUGGGAGUUGCAUGGAAGAAUUGGGGAGUGAGGCAGGGGACUGGAAAGGGAGCAGAGCACAUAAUUUUGGGGCCUUUGAAACAAGUAACAGUGACAAAAAACCUCACUCUGGAAUCAGUAACCUCUCCCCCGCACCCUCCCCAACACUUUCAGGAGAUGAGUAUAUAGAGUGGGGACCAGGAGGAAGUAACCUCUGUAACCCAGAAGUGGCUAAAGUGUUGAACUUUGAGCUUCUCUAAGGAGAGCUGGCUAUCUGGCUGAGCUGCCAAGUACUCCUGUCUUUCAGAAAUUGACAGCUGAAGUAUUUGGUCUUGGUUUCCCACUGAAGAGGAAUGUGUAGAAUCACUGCAGAGCAGAAGAAAUUAAAUUUUGAAUAUUAAUGCCUGAUCUUUUAAGUUAUCUGACUAAAAACAGAAGAGUGAUCAUAAGCCCAACCCUAGGUAUCAGUGUAUUAUGGCUAGCAAGGAGUUAAGAAGCUUUGUCUAUUCAGCAGUCAUAAUUGAAUGUGUAGUUUGCAAGCCUGCCAAAUUGCUAAACCUAGAUUUCUCAUAUUAGAUAAUGUGUAAUAAAAGACAGCUGUUGCCAGCAUAUGCUGUGAAUUGCACACCAGUUCCUCAUUCAUGAUUUUUGGCGCCAUCACUACAACCCUUAGAAAAGGCUCUGACUGGAGGGCUGUCUGGGGAACAUAGACCCCACUGGUCAGAUCCUUGAAUAAGGCUGCUCGCCCUAGGGAAAGCGGGGCAGGAAAGACUUUUUUUUUUUUUCAAAGUGCAAAACCCUUGAUAAGACCUUAGACACACUUCAUUUCACUUUAGGCAGGUAGUUUGGUGUGUGAGCUAGUUUCGAACCCUGGGAACAUUCCUUUCCACAUCGCCUGAGUCUGACAGCCCGGAUCAAAAACAAGCAGGCUUUGUGUCAAGACGUGGCACGUGUCAGAGAAUUUGACGCUUGCUUUGACCAGAUCAAGUUCUUUAAGUGACUUUUCCUGGUCUCAAAGAAAGCUUGUUACUGUGGAGAAGCAGGAUAAUGAAACAUUUGGAUUUGAAAUUCAGUCUUACAGGCCCCAGAAUCAGAAUGCCUGCUCCUCGGAAAUGUUCACUUUGAUAUGCAAAAUACAGGAGGACAGCCCAGCUCACUGUGCUGGCCUGCAAGCUGGUGAUGUCCUUGCAAAUAUCAAUGGUGUGAGCACAGAAGGUUUUACCUACAAACAAGUCGUUGACCUGAUCAGAUCGUCCGGAAACCUGCUAACGAUAGAGACUCUUAAUGGAACAAUGAUUCUGAAAAGAACGGAGCUUGAAGCAAAGCUGCAGGUUUUAAAGCAAACUUUGAAACAAAAAUGGGUGGAGUACAGAUCUCUGCAGUUACAGGAACAUCGUCUGCUUCAUGGUGAUGCAGCUAAUUGCCCCAGUUUGGAAAACAUGGACUUGGAUGAAUUGUCUUUGUUUGGACCCCUGCCUGGGCCAGGCCCAGCCCUUGUGGACCGGAAUCGAUUAUCCAGUGAGAGCAGCUGUAAGAGCUGGCUGAGCUCCAUGACGAUGGACAGUGAAGAUGGCUACCAGACGUGUGUGUCUGAGGACUCCAGCAGGGGUGCCUUCAGUCGGCAGACGAGUACAGAUGAUGAGUGCUUUAUCCCCAAGGAGGGGGAUGAUUUUCUGAGGAGGUCAUCUUCAAGGAGGAACCGGAGCAUCAGUAACACCAGCAGCGGAUCCAUGUCUCCCUUGUGGGAGGGCAACUUAUCAAGCAUGUUUGGGACCCUGCCCCGGAAGAGCAGAAAGGGAAGUGUCCGAAAGCAACUCUUGAAAUUUAUCCCUGGCCUUCAUCGUGCUGUGGAAGAGGAAGAAAGUCGCUUUUGACGGAUUGUGGUGUCCUUUCAAAUUAGCUUAUUUCACAAAUAUCUCUAGACUCACCCAGAUCCCAGCUUGGUGGGAAAGUGCAGAAGAAUUGCAAAACUGACAUCCCAUUUCACAGCAAUAGUGACCUUUAUUUAAAUUGUUGUGUUAUAGUUUAUGCUUCUUAAAUCAUUUUUCAACCUAAACAGCCAAUUUCUAAGCAGACAGGAAAACUAAAUAAUAAGUUAAUUAAUAUAACAAAGAUGCAGGUUCCUGCUCAUUCCAGUAAUGUCUUUGAAAGCAAAACUAAUAUUUAUUUUCUAGAUUAUCCCUGUGAAUAAUUGAGAACUUUUUGGAGUCAAGUAUGAAUAAAGGUGUGGCAGAAUAUAAUAAUCUGGACUAUUUUCUAUAGGAUAAUUGCUGGGUUAUAAAAUCUUAGGUUUGCUUAUGCCCAGUAGCUCCUGCGGAGGCUUAAUAAUAGGCAAUUUUGAAUUUGUUCAAACCUGUAAUGGCUUGUAAACAAAGAUGACCAUCAGCUGUUUCUCACAUCUAUAGUGACAAUAAAGCGGGAAGUAUAAGAUUUAAUAGGAGGGGUUAAGGUUCAUGAGAACCAUGGAAAGAUGUGGUCUGAGAUGGGUGCUGCAAAGAUCAUAAUAAAGUCAUUUUUAUAGACAGUCUAAACAAAAUGGGUGGGGAUGUCGUGUUUUUUGCCCAAUUCAGCUUUUGUUCUGCCUGAACAUUAAUGGCAAGUCUAGAACUCUCCGAAUCCUACAGCUUUGUAAUUUUUUUUCUACAAAUGUCUAACAUCCAAAACUGAGGGUUGGGAAAAGGACUUCCCUCCUGUAGUUUUUUUCAUAUUACUUCUCACUUUAUAUCUUAUAUUCUAAAUAGCUAUCACCUCAGCAGUCUUUUGCCUAUUGGUUAUGUUAGUAUCACAUUACUUCUAGCCUUUCAAUUACUCCAUGUUUUAUUUAAUAUCCAUUGAAGUCUAUGAAUUCUCUGUUCUGGUGGCACAGCUAUUCAUAACCUAUAUUCUAGAGUAGACAAUCUGGACUAUGUAAUAAAUAGUCUGCUGAUUUUAA